UAAGAAUAUACUUCAUCCAUUCCUUUAAAGGGAAGUUUUUUCUUUUUUUUCUUUUUUUUGUGUGUGUGUGUGUGGUUUUUUGCUUUUGUUUUUGUUUUUUAGUUUUUAAUUUUUUAAAUGAAAGUUUGGUGGGGGGUGGAAUUUAGAUGUUCUUUUCCUUUAUUUUUCAUUUUUUUUUUAAACACAGCACUUGCACUCAAUGUUUUUGUUUUCAAAAUCUACAAAAGCACACAGAGCAGGGAAGAAAGAUCCUUUUCAUACUCCCCUCCCCAAAGGUAACCACCAUGCAUCAACAGUUUGGUGUGUAACAUUUUAGAUCUUUCUGCAGUUACAUUUAUGUAUGUAUGUUUACAAAGGUUUUGGAGAGCUUUGGGCGAUUUUUUAGUUUUGGGGUUUUUUGAAAUAUAAACAGGAUCAUUCUGCAUGUAUUGUUCUGCAUCCUGCUUUUUUUACUCAGUGAUACAUGGAGAGAAUCUUUUUGUGUUAUGAAUUGAAUUCAUUUUUUUUUAAAGCUGCUGCAUGGUACUCCAGAGUAUGGAUGAACCAUAAUUCAUCUACUAUUUCUCUAUUAAUGGACAUUUAUGUUGUUAACAGUUUUUCAUUAUUACAAAUAGUGGUGCUUUUGAACAUCCUUAACGUAUAUCUUUGUGUACUUGUGCAGGUAUUUCUGGCAGUAUAGAAACAGUAAGUGGACUUGCUGGUCAAAUGGUAGCUACAUUUAAAAAACAGUGAUGGCUACUGCUUAAUUGUAUAUCAAAAGAGAUUUAUACCAGUAACUUUCAUACAUUUCUGUUUCCUUAUUCUCUCACUUAAAUUCAACAACAUCAUUCCUCUUAACAUUUUUGCCAAUGGUGAAAAGUAUUUCGUAUACAAAUUUACAUAUUCUUACUCAUGUGGUUAAGUUUCUUACAUGUAUUUGUUGAACUUCCUGUGAAUUGCUUAUUCAUAUCUUUUUCUCACUUUUUCCUAAUGAGUUUUGUUAUUUUUCUUUAAUGAAUUUUAGGAAUGCUUUAUGUAUUGUUGCUAUUAAUCUUCAAUUUUACGUAUAUUUGCAUAGUAAUUGCCUACUUUUAGCUCUUCGUUGUCAUACAGACAUUUUUACAUUUUUAUUUACUUAAAUUUAUCAAUCUUUUUCUUUAGAGUUUCUCUGGAUUUUGUGUUUUAUUGAGGAGGGUUAUCCCCAUCCCAAGAAUAUAUAUAUGUUUUAUAGUAAUUCUUUAUAAUACUUCUAUAACUUUGUUUUCAACCUAUCUGAAGUAAUAAUUUUCAUUUGAUAUGAGUUGGAAAUCUGUUUUAAUUAGGACUUUUUCAAUUGCAAGUGACCAAACCAACUUAAACUAGCUUAAGUGAAGAGGGAAUUUAAUUAGCUCAUGUAGUUGGGAAGUCCGAGCCAUCAUCAGGUAUAACUGGACCCUCAGGUAUCAAACUCUUUGUUUUCCUCUCUCUCUCACCUUUUAGGUCUACAUAUAUUUAUGUGUGUUAACCUCAUUCUCUCCCAGUACAGACAGGCUAUUCCCAUGUGGCAGGGAAGAUGGCACCAGCAAUUUGUAUUUAUAUGUUUCCAAGGUCUGUGACCCAAAGGCAAGGCCCCUACUUCUGCUCCAAAUCAGAAGCCCUUGAGGAAGGAAUUUGAGUGGCUUAUCUUGGAUCAUAUUGUUUCUAACCCUAUGGCCAGGGCAGGCAAGGUACUACGAUUGAUGCCUCCAGCAAAAGUUGGGUAGGAAUGGUUUUCUAAGGAAACAGGGACGCUGCAAAUAUUAUAGCAUAGUAAAUAUCUACACUUCCAUCCUUUGGUAGCUCAGCACGUGUGUGUACUCACAUUUGUUCUCAUACAUACAAUUCAAAAAUGGUUCUGCCUAAUAUAAUGCAAAGAUUUCACCCACAACUUAAAACUUUUUCAAAAACCUCUUUCCCACAGUUACAUCCUGUAAUUGUAUCUAGACCUAAAUCUAGUAUUUCUCUGUGUGUAUAUUAAUUUCAGUAGAUCUGGGCCGGGCUCGGUGGCUCACACCUGUAAUCCCAGCACUUUGGGAGGCCAAGGCGGGCGGAUCACGAGGUCAGGAGUUCGAGACCAGUCUGGCCAACAUAGUGAAACCCUGUCUCUACUAAAAAUACAAAAAAUACUAGCCGGGCAUGGUGGUGUGUGCCUGUAAUCCCAGCUACUGGGGAGGCUGAGGCAGGAGAAUUGCUUGAACCCAGGAGGCAGAGGUUGCAGUGAGCCGAGAUCGUGCCACUGCACUCCAGUCUGGGUGACAGAACGAGACUCCGUCUCAAAAAAAAAAAAAAAAAAAAAAAAUUAAAUUCCAGUAGAUCUCGAGGUGGCUUAUCUUGAUCUCACAAUCCAUGAGCCACAUUAUGAAUUUAACUGCCUAUGACACUCAUAAACAUAGUAGAGGGUGUUCUUUAAUAAAACUGGAUGCCAUUGUUUUUCUGGGAGAAUGGCUGUGUUUGAGAGGUGAGAAACAUAUAAGAAGAUUCCCCUUCUGGAGGCCAUUCUGUUUUACCUGCCUAGUUCCUGCUGUCUGUUACUGGGGUUGGGUUGCUGGGGACUUCUAUAGGAUUAAACAAUCAUAUAACCCUAUUUGGCAGGUUUGGGGUUUUUUCUGACAGUAGCACUCACUUGUAGAUUCCUAGGUUCCCAGCUAGUACUUAAUGCCCAGUAACUUGCUUUAGGAUCCAUGAAGGUGAACACCCUCCACUUCCUCAGUUUAUCUGUUUAGUAGGCCAAUAGUCCUAGUCCUCAGGUGAAGAGUUUGUGUAGGCUUCUGCCUGCUGGUAUCAUUAAACAGUGAGCUGCAGAGGCUGAUGUAGAUCUGUAGCCUGCUGCCAGGCUGCAUCACAAGGAUCCACUGCUUUAUAAUAGGAGGAAUAUGGCCUUUGGGCAGAGGGUGUUCAGUAAAGACCUCUACCCUCAGUUUAGUUCUUUUUCUCCAUUCCUUUAAGUCUUACCCCUGUGGUAAUUUUCUCCUCCUUUCCCUUAUUUGCACUAAAUUUAGCAAGUGAUAAAGGAUUGACUCUGAGCAGUAUUGGAUUGUUGGCUCUGAAUUAGGAAGCUUUUUAAAAGCACUGUGUCAUUCUCUUUCUCUUUUCGGGAAAUCUGACCCAGACCAAAUGAUGUCUAAAAAGUAUCUAUUACAGGACUUUAUAGAUGGUCCCAAGAACUAACCACCAUAGUUCAACAUCUUGGCAUAAAACUCCAUGAUCUGAAGGCCAGGCGCAGUGGCUCACGCCUGUAAUCCCAGCACUUUGGGAGGCUGAGACGGGUGGAUCACUGGAGGUCAGGGGUUCAAGACCAGCCUGACCAACAUGGUGAAACCCCGUCUCUACUAAAAAUACAAAAAUUAGCUGGGCAUGGUGGCGGGCGCCUGUAAUCCCAGCUACUUGGGAGGCUGAGGCAGGAGAAUCGCUUGAACCCAGGAGGCAGAGGUUGCAGUGAGCCGAGAUCGCACCACUGCACUCCAGCCUGGGCGACAAGAGCGAAACUCCAUCUCAAAAAAAAGAAAAAAAACCUCCAUGAUCUGAGACCCAAGAGAAAAUUGAUAGUCUGACCAACUGCUUUGCUACCACACAUCCAAAGUGACUUGCUUUCCAGCCUGGGGUGGCAAGAUGCUCAGUACCCUCUCUCCAUUUUGACUUAUUAUUUAAGGAGGGCAAAGAGGUACUGGUAGUUAACUCUCAAGGAGAAAUUUCACGGUUGAGCACCAAAAAGGAAGUGAUCAUGAAAGGAAAUAUCAACAAUUAUUUUAAAUUGGGUCAAGAAGGGAAGUAUCGCGUCUACCACAAUCAAUACUCCACCAAUUCAUUUGCUUUGAAUAAGCACCAGCACAGAGAAGACCAUGAUAAGAGAAGGCAUCUUGCACAUAAGUUCUGUCUGACUCCAGCAGGAGAGUUCAAAUGGAACGGUUCUGUCCAUGGGUCCAAAGUUCUUACCAUAUCUACUCUGAGACUGACUAUCACCCAAUUAGAAAACAACAUCCCUUCAUCCUUUCUUCAUCCCAACUGGGCAUCACAUAGGGCAAAUUGGAUCAAGGCAGUUCAGAUGUGUAGCAAACCCAGAGAAUUUGCAUUGGCUUUAGCCAUUUUGGAGUGUGCAGUUAAACCAGUUGUGAUGCUACCAAUAUGGCGAGAAUCUUUAGGACAUACCAGGUUACACCGGAUGACAUCAAUUGAAAGAGAAGAAAAGGAGAAAGUCAAAAAAAAAGAGAAGAAACAGGAAGAAGAAGAAACGAUGCAGCAAGCGACAUGGGUAAAAUACACAUUUCCAGUUAAGCAUCAGGUUUGGAAACAAAAAGGUGAAGAGUACAGAGUGACAGGAUAUGGUGGUUGGAGCUGGAUUAGUAAAACUCAUGUUUAUAGGUUUGUUCCUAAAUUGCCAGGCAAUACUAAUGUGAAUUACAGAAAGUCGUUAGAAGGAACCAAAAAUAAUAUGGAUGAAAAUAUGGAUGAGUCAGAUAAAAGAAAAUGUUCACGAAGUCCAAAAAAAAUAAAAAUAGAGCCUGAUUCUGAAAAAGAUGAGGUAAAAGGUUCAGAUGCUGCAAAAGGAGCAGACCAAAAUGAAAUGGAUAUCUCAAAGAUUACUGAGAAGAAGGACCAAGAUGUGAAGGAGCUCUUAGAUUCUGACAGUGAUAAACCCUGCAAGGAAGAACCAAUGGAAGUAGACGAUGACAUGAAAACAGAGUCACAUGUAAAUUGUCAGGAGAGUUCUCAAGUAGAUGUGGUCAAUGUUAGUGAGGGUUUUCAUCUAAGGACUAGUUACAAAAAGAAAACAAAAUCAUCCAAACUAGAUGGACUUCUUGAAAGGAGAAUUAAACAGUUUACACUGGAAGAAAAACAGCGACUCGAAAAAAUCAAGUUGGAGGGUGGAAUUAAGGGUAUAGGAAAGACUUCUACAAAUUCUUCAAAAAAUCUCUCUGAAUCACCAGUAAUAACGAAAGCAAAAGAAGGGUGUCAGAGUGACUCGAUGAGACAAGAACAGAGCCCAAAUGCAAAUAAUGAUCAACCUGAGGACUUGAUUCAGGGAUGUUCAGAAAGUGAUUCCUCAGUUCUUAGAAUGAGUGAUCCUAGUCAUACCACAAACAAACUUUAUCCAAAAGAUCGAGUGUUAGAUGAUGUCUCCAUUCGGAGCCCAGAAACAAAAUGUCCGAAACAAAAUUCCAUUGAAAAUGACAUAGAAGAAAAAGUCUCUGACCUUGCCAGUAGAGGCCAGGAACCCAGUAAGAGUAAAACAAAAGGAAAUGAUUUUUUCAUCGAUGACUCUAAACUAGCCAGUGCAGAUGAUAUUGGUACUUUGAUCUGUAAGAACAAAAAACCGCUCAUACAGGAGGAAAGUGACACCAUUGUUUCUUCUUCCAAGAGUGCUUUACAUUCAUCAGUGCCUAAAAGUACCAAUGACAGAGAUGCCACACCUCUGUCAAGAGCAAUGGACUUUGAAGGAAAACUGGGAUGUGACUCUGAAUCUAAUAGCACUUUGGAAAAUAGUUCUGAUACCGUGUCUAUUCAGGAUAGCAGUGAAGAAGAUAUGAUUGUUCAGAAUAGCAAUGAAAGCAUUUCUGAACAGUUCAGAACUCGAGAACAAGAUGUUGAAGUCUUGGAGCCGUUAAAGUGUGAGUUGGUUUCUGGUGAGUCCACUGGAAACUGUGAGGACAGGCUGCCGGUCAAGGGGACUGAAGCAAAUGGUAAAAAACCAAGUCAGCAGAAGAAAUUAGAGGAGAGACCAGUUAAUAAAUGUAGUGAUCAAAUAAAGCUAAAAAAUACCACUGACAAAAAGAAUAAUGAAAAUCGAGAGUCUGAAAAGAAAGGACAGAGAACAAGUACAUUUCAAAUAAAUGGAAAAGAUAAUAAACCCAAAAUAUAUUUGAAAGGUGAAUGCUUGAAAGAAAUUUCUGAGAGUAGAGUAGUAAGUGGUAAUGUUGAACCAAAGGUUAAUAAUAUAAAUAAAAUAAUCCCUGAGAAUGAUAUUAAAUCAUUGACUGUUAAAGAAUCUGCUAUAAGGCCAUUCAUUAAUGGUGAUGUCAUCAUGGAAGAUUUUAAUGAAAGAAACAGCUCCGAAACAAAAUCGCAUUUGCUGAGUUCUUCAGAUGCUGAAGGUAACUACCGAGAUAGCCUUGAGACCCUGCCAUCAACCAAAGAGUCUGACAGUACACAGACGACCACACCCUCAGCAUCUUGUCCAGAAAGCAAUUCAGUUAAUCAGGUAGAAGAUAUGGAAAUAGAAACCUCAGAAGUUAAGAAAGUUACUUCAUCACCUAUUACUUCUGAAGAGGAAUCUAAUCUCAGUAAUGACUUUAUUGAUGAAAAUGGUCUGCCCAUCAACAAAAAUGAAAAUGUCAAUGGAGAAUCUAAAAGAAAAACCGUCAUCACAGAAGUCACCACGAUGACCUCCACAGUGGCCACAGAAUCAAAAACUGUGAUCAAGGUAGAAAAAGGCGAUAAGCAAACUGUGGUUUCUUCCACAGAAAAUUGUGCAAAAUCCACUGUCACAACCACCACUACAACAGUGACCAAGCUUUCCACACCCUCCACAGGCGGCAGUGUGGACAUCAUCUCUGUAAAGGAGCAGAGCAAAACCGUGGUCACCACGACAGUGACAGACUCCCUGACCACCACGGGAGGCACACUGGUUACAUCUAUGACUGUGAGCAAAGAGUAUUCCACACGAGACAAAGUGAAACUGAUGAAAUUUUCAAGACCAAAGAAGACUCGUUCAGGUACAGCUCUGCCAUCCUAUAGAAAAUUUGUUACCAAGAGCAGCAAGAAGAGCAUUUUUGUUUUGCCUAAUGAUGACUUAAAAAAGUUGGCCCGAAAAGGAGGAAUCCGAGAGGUCCCUUAUUUUAAUUACAAUGCAAAACCUGCUUUGGAUAUAUGGCCAUAUCCUUCUCCUAGACCGACCUUUGGCAUCACUUGGAGGUAUAGACUUCAGACAGUAAAGUCCUUAGCUGGAGUGAGCCUGAUGUUACGGUUACUGUGGGCAAGUUUGAGAUGGGAUGAUAUGGCGGCCAAGGCUCCUCCAGGAGGAGGGACUACACGGACAGAAACAUCCGAAACUGAAAUCACAACAACAGAAAUAAUUAAGAGGAGAGAUGUUGGUCCUUAUGGCAUUCGAUCUGAAUAUUGUAUCAGGAAAAUCAUUUGUCCCAUUGGAGUUCCAGAAACACCAAAAGAAACGCCUACACCUCAGAGGAAAGGCCUUCGAUCAAGUGCACUGCGGCCAAAGAGACCAGAAACGCCCAAGCAAACUGGCCCUGUUAUUAUUGAAACCUGGGUAGCAGAAGAAGAACUGGAAUUGUGGGAGAUCAGGGCAUUUGCUGAGAGAGUGGAGAAAGAAAAGGCACAAGCAGUUGAGCAACAGGCUAAGAAACGACUGGAGCAGCAGAAGCCGACAGUGAUUGCAACUUCCACUACUUCCCCAACAAGCAGUACAACCAGCACCAUCUCUCCAGCACAGAAGGUUAUGGUGGCCCCCAUAAGUGGCUCAGUUACAACUGGAACCAAAAUGGUACUAACUACUAAAGUUGGAUCUCCAGCUACAGUAACAUUCCAACAAAACAAGAACUUUCAUCAAACCUUUGCUACAUGGGUUAAGCAAGGCCAGUCAAAUUCAGCCACCAGCACAGCUGCCACAUCUGCUACAACCAUUGCCAGCACAGGUCAGACGUUCCAAAUUACAGGCAAUCCAGUCACUAUGGCAGGAAAAGUAAUUACCAAACUGCCACUUCCUGCAAACAGCAAGAUUGUCGCUGUAAAUGUGCCAGCAACACAAGGAGGCGUUGUUCAAGUACAGCAGAAAGUCCUGGGUAUCAUUCCAUCAAGUACAGGUACCAGUCAGCAAACCUUUACUUCAUUCCAGCCCAGGACAGCAACAGUCACAAUUAGGCCCAAUACCUCAGGCUCUGGAGGAACCACAAGCAAUUCACAAGUAAUCACAGGGCCUCAGAUUCGCCCUGGUAUGACCGUGAUUAGAACACCACUCCAACAGUCAACACUAGGAAAGGCAAUUAUUCGAACACCUGUGAUGGUACAGCCAGGUGCUCCUCAGCAAGUGAUGACUCAAAUCAUCAGGGGGCAGCCUGUCUCCACUGCAGUCUCCGCCCCUAACACGGUUUCCUCAACACCUGGGCAGAAAAGCUUAACUUCAGCAACGUCCACUUCAAAUAUACAGUCUUCAGCCUCACAACCCCCUCGCCCCCAACAAGGACAAGUGAAGCUCACCAUGGCUCAACUUACUCAGUUAACACAGGGCCACGGUGGCAAUCAAGGUUUGACAGUAGUAAUUCAAGGACAAGGUCAAACUACUGGACAGUUGCAGUUGAUACCUCAAGGGGUGACUGUACUCCCAGGCCCAGGCCAGCAGCUAAUGCAAGCUGCAAUGCCAAAUGGUACUGUUCAGCGAUUCCUCUUUACCCCAUUGGCAACAACAGCCACCACAGCCAGCACCACCACCACCACUGUUUCCACGACAGCAGCAGGUACAGGUGAACAAAGGCAGAGUAAACUGUCACCCCAGAUGCAGGUACAUCAAGACAAAACCCUGCCACCAGCUCAGUCAUCAAGUGUGGGUCCAGCAGAAGCCCAGCCACAGACUGCUCAGCCUUCAGCUCAGCCCCAGCCCCAAACCCAGCCCCAGUCCCCAGCUCAGCCUGAAGUUCAGACUCAGCCUGAAGUUCAGACCCAAACAACUGUUUCAUCCCAUGUCCCUUCUGAAGCACAACCCACCCACGCACAGUCAUCCAAGCCCCAAGUUGCAGCACAGUCUCAGCCUCAAAGUAAUGUCCAAGGACAGUCUCCUGUUCGUGUCCAAAGUCCAUCACAGACUCGAAUACGUCCAUCAACUCCAUCCCAACUGUCUCCUGGACAACAAUCCCAGGUUCAGACUACAACCUCACAACCGAUUCCAAUUCAACCACAUACAUCUCUUCAGAUACCUUCCCAAGGCCAGCCACAGUCACAACCCCAGGUACAGUCUUCAACUCAAACUCUUUCAUCAGGACAAACUUUAAAUCAAGUUACUGUUUCAUCCCCAUCCCGUCCUCAGCUACAAAUACAGCAGCCACAGCCCCAAGUCAUUGCUGUGCCUCAGCUGCAACAACAAGUCCAGGUUCUCUCUCAGAUCCAGUCACAGGUUGUGGCUCAGAUACAGGCUCAGCAAAGUGGUGUGCCCCAGCAAAUCAAACUCCAGUUACCUAUCCAAAUUCAGCAAAGCAGUGCUGUGCAGACUCACCAGAUUCAGAAUGUGGUUACAGUGCAGGCAGCCAGUGUGCAAGAGCAGUUGCAAAGGGUUCAGCAACUCAGGGAUCAGCAGCAAAAGAAGAAACAGCAACAGAUAGAAAUUAAGCGUGAACACACCCUCCAAGCUUCUAAUCAAAGUGAAAUCAUUCAGAAACAGGUGGUGAUGAAGCAUAAUGCUGUAAUAGAACAUUUAAAACAGAAAAAGAGCAUGACUCCAGCUGAAAGAGAAGAGAAUCAAAGAAUGAUUGUCUGUAACCAGGUGAUGAAGUAUAUUUUGGAUAAGAUAGAUAAAGAAGAAAAACAGGCAGCAAAAAAACGGAAGCGUGAAGAGAGUGUGGAGCAGAAACGUAGCAAGCAGAAUGCCACUAAGCUGUCAGCUCUGCUCUUCAAGCACAAAGAGCAGCUCAGAGCCGAGAUCCUGAAGAAGAGAGCACUCCUGGACAAGGAUCUGCAAAUUGAAGUGCAGGAAGAGCUGAAGAGAGACCUGAAAAUUAAGAAAGAAAAAGACCUGAUGCAGUUGGCUCAGGCCACAGCAGUAGCUGCACCCUGCCCCCCAGUGACACCAGCUCCUCCAGCCCCUCCAGCCCCUCCACCUUCACCUCCCCCUCCACCUGCUGUGCAACACACAGGCCUUCUGUCCACGCCCACCUUACCUGCUGCUUCCCAGAAGAGGAAGCGGGAAGAGGAAAAAGACUCCAGCUCAAAGUCCAAGAAAAAGAAAAUGAUCUCUACUACCUCAAAGGAAACUAAGAAGGACACAAAGCUUUACUGUAUCUGUAAAACGCCUUAUGAUGAAUCUAAGUUCUAUAUUGGCUGUGAUCUUUGUACUAACUGGUAUCAUGGAGAAUGUGUUGGCAUCACAGAAAAGGAGGCUAAGAAAAUGGAUGUGUACAUCUGUAAUGAUUGUAAACGGGCACAAGAGGGCAGCAGUGAGGAAUUGUACUGUAUCUGCAGAACACCUUAUGAUGAGUCACAAUUUUAUAUUGGCUGUGAUCGGUGUCAGAAUUGGUACCAUGGGCGCUGCGUUGGCAUCUUGCAAAGUGAGGCAGAGCUCAUUGAUGAGUAUGUCUGUCCACAGUGCCAGUCAACAGAGGAUGCCAUGACAGUGCUCACGCCACUAACAGAGAAGGAUUAUGAGGGGUUGAAGAGGGUGCUCCGUUCCUUACAGGCCCAUAAGAUGGCCUGGCCUUUCCUUGAACCAGUAGACCCUAAUGAUGCACCAGAUUAUUAUGGUGUUAUUAAGGAACCUAUGGACCUUGCCACCAUGGAAGAAAGAGUACAAAGACGAUAUUAUGAAAAGCUGACGGAAUUUGUGGCAGAUAUGACCAAAAUUUUUGAUAACUGUCGUUACUACAAUCCAAGUGACUCCCCAUUUUACCAGUGUGCAGAAGUUCUCGAAUCAUUCUUUGUACAGAAAUUGAAAGGCUUCAAAGCUAGCAGGUCUCAUAACAACAAACUGCAGUCUACAGCUUCUUAAAGUUCAGCGUGUUAACCUAACAUAAAACACAGCAAGAAUCUGGUUGUCUGAACUAUUUUAAAUUAAGGAGCCAGAUGUUUUUAGUCAGGCUAUCCUGACAAGACUUGACCUAAACUUCGUUUUUAUUGGUCAUAACAGUCCAAUUAUAUUCUUGGCCAAUUUUGUCCAACGGACAAGAAAAAAGCAAAGUCAACGACACCAUUAUCUUGUCAAGAUCAGAUGGUUUUACUAUUGUGGCAGAAGCGAGAAAACUUUGUUUAUUGAAAAAAAAAGAAAAAGAAAGCAAGAAAAAAAGAUACUAUGGGGUCAAGUGUAACUCCAUGGAAAUGCCACGUCUGCUCUUCAGUGAAGAAGCUGGUUUAGAGUCUCACAGAAAACUUUUGACUGUAUUUAUUUAUUGUUGCAAAAAAGACGCUUUUUUAUUGCUGCCCUCAUUUGUCAGCUAAUUAUUUUUUCUUAUAAAAUCCAGCCCCGGUUACAUAUAAUCAUCUGUAUCUUAUCAUGAUUCCUGUAGGUAAAAGUACAAGACGACCUCUAGAUGUCUUUUCUUUCUAUGAAAGGAGCUGCUAUGUACACAUGUGCACACACACACAACUGGGAAUCAACAAUGAGUUUAUUGUUCAUGGUAGAUUAAAAUUAAGCUUGCAUAAAGGUUGGGCUAAGUGGUCCUGGACUACAGACUCUGUUGCCUUGAAUAUAACAGUACAAUUUGUCAAUUACUCUGCACCAGGCUAAAAUGAGUAAAAUCUAUUUGAAGGUAUCUUGUUUGUAAACAUUUGUCAGAUUCUAAUUUUUUUCUUUUGUAUUAAAAUUCAACUAUGGAUGUAUAUGAAACAAAAUAAAUGGAGAUAAUUUUUCUCCCACAGACAGAGGUGUCUUUGAAUGUGCGCUAAUGAUUAUCUGUAAGCCUUUGUGGGGAGGGAGGCCUGCAAGGUCAUGAAAGGCAGAAGAGUCUAAUUGUGCCUGGAUUUCUCCAGGACAGCAGUGGCCCCUCGUUUUAUCAUUCCCAGUCCAUUGUCAUCACGUCAGAGAAAAAUCUUCAGGGGUGCUAAUCCUGUUGCAUCAGUUGAUCAUACUAACGAGAACGGUAAUGCGACAAGAUACACAUUGCCUUCAUCUGUACAUUCUGUGAUACCAGGCAAAUUACCAAUUACACACAGCUACUUAUAUUUUAUGAAGGGCAUUUUUUAGAUGACCUCAUCCUCUGUGUUAUUUGUUGAUUGGGUUUGUUUUCUGUUUGUUGGUUUGUUUGUUUCUUCCACGUAAGGAAAAGUAGUGUAAACAGUAGCGAGAAAAUGGAAACCACAGAGGAAGAUGUAUUUUGCAUGUUUUUCCUUUCAGUGUUCUUACACGUUGUAUCACUGCAUUGUGGUAAUAGCUUCUAUAAAAUCUGCCAUAGUUGGAUUAUGCAGCUUUGCAAAAAUUUUUACUAGAUUUUGCACUAACUCAUAUUAGCUUUGUCCUACCAACUUCUGGAAUUUAUCUAAUUAUUGUUUUUCAAAGUUUCUUUCCUUUUAAUGUUUCCCUGCUAUGCAAAACCUUUCCCAGACCUCAGUUUCUUAAAAGAAAGAUGUUGCUACAGUUCCCGAUUCUUUCUUAUUACAGGCUCAGGUGUACAGGUUAUUCUGGGUUAAUUUUAUCUAAUGAAGCCCAUUCCUUUUUGUACAUAAAGAUGUCACUUAAACUUAUGCUUACAAACUAAAGACUAAUCGCUCAAUAUGAAAACAUGAAAAAAUUUUUGCUUAAAGUAUUAAGAUGGAAGUAGUUAAAUAUGGGUUAUUUUGUCCUUUUACUUUUUUAAAAAAUGUUACAUAUUGUAUGCACUGUGCUGAUGCAAGAAUUCUACAUUUUAAUGAGUUAUAAAAUUAUUCUGCAUCUCAUCACGUCACAGUAUUUCUGUACUAUUUAUUCAUAUAUAUAAAUAUAUAUGGGCUUAAUCAUUUAAAAUUUGUUGCAGCAAGAACUUUCCUACCUGUAGGCAAUAGAUUGCUAUGUUUUUAACAAAUUGUGGCAAAUUCUAAACAGCAAUUCUUUUGUACGUAAUAGGACAUUUCAUCCUAGAAAAAUAAAGUAAUGUUUUUGACAUUGGA